UGUAUGUGUAGUCUGCUCUGUGUAUUGAGAGCUCCUGGAAGGCUAAGGGAAGAACUGGCCUCUGGGAAGACGCUAGUGUCGCUACUACUUUGUUUCCUUAGCAACAGUCCUGACGGGGAGCUCCUUCAUUGUAUUCUGUUCCUACCGAUACACGUUGCUCCUUUUUUUUUUUUGAGAUGACUCUCAUGCUGUCGCUCAGGCUGGAGUGCAAUGGCACAAUCUUGGCUCACUGCAACCUUCGCCUCCCAGGUUCAAGUGAUUCUCCUGCCUCAGCCUCCCAAGUAGCUGAGAUUACAGGCACUCACUACCACACCCAGAUAAUUUUUUUAUUUUUAGUAGAGAUUGGGUUUCACUAUGUUGGCCGGGCUGAUCUCGAACUCUUGACCUCAUGUGGUCCACCCACCUCGGCCUCCCAAAGUGCUAGAAUUACAGGCAUGAGCCACCACGCCCAGCCACCUUUUCUUUUUUUUCUUUUGAAACAGGGUCUUCCUCUGUUGCUCAGGCUGGAGUGCAGUGGAGUGAUUACAGCUCACUGCAGCCUUGACCUCCUGGGUUCUGGUGAUUUCCCACCUCAGCCUCCUGAGUAGCUGGGACUACAGGCAUGCACCACCAUGUCUGACUAAUUUUUUGUAUUUUUUGUAGAAAUGGGGUUUCUCUAUGUUGCCUAGACUGGUCUCGAAUUCCUGGGCUCAAGCAGUCUGCCCACAUCAGCCUCCCAAAGUGCUUGGAUUACAGGCAUGAGCCACUACACCCAGCUGCCCCAGUUUUUCAUUUGCAUAAUUUUCUAUGCAAAUUUUUUGCAUUUUUUUAGUUCAGCCAAAUUAGCUGAGGUCUAAAGCACUCCUUUUAGUGCAGUCACAUUAGUUGAGGUUUCAACAAAUUCAUUAACAGUAAACCAGUGGUCCUCAACCCAGCUUCAUAUUAGGAUCACUUGGGGAAUUUUUAAAUAACACAGCUGUCCCUGGCCCACCCCAGACCAAUUAAAUGGGAAUCUCUGAGGGUAGGGUUUGGUGGUCAGUGUUGUUUUUUUUUAAUGCUCCCCAGAUAAUUCAGAUGUCUAGAAAGGAUGGAGAACCACUGCUCCAAGGCAUUUGAUCCUUCAUUAAGGAUAAUUUAACCUAACUCUACACAUUCAAUUACAUCUGUUAUCUUAUUGUUAUUCUUUCCAUCUUACAUUUCCACCCAACAUUGGCCUCUUUCCUUCCUUGUAUUCCCCAGACAUGCUGUCACCUCAACAGCAUUUUUUUUUUGAGACAGGGUCUUGCUCUGUCACCUAGCUGGAGUGCAGUGGCGUGAUCAUAGCUCACUGCAGCCUAGACCUCCCAGGCUCAAGCGAUCCUCCCACCUCACCUCAGCCUCCCGAGUAACUGUGACUACAGGCAUGUGCCACCAUGGCUAAUUUUUGUGGUUUUUGUUGAGACGAGGUUUUGCCCUAUUGUUCAGGCUGGUCUCGAACUCCUGGAUUCAAGUGAUCCACCUGACUUGGCCUCCUAAGGUGCUGGGAUUACAUGCAUGAGCCACCACUGCUGGCCAUCAUACCCUUUUAUCUAUCUGAAUGUUUUGCAGAUACUCUCAGUUUCUUCCUUCAGCUUCUUCAGAUCUUUGCUCAAAUGUCACCUUCUCAGUGAGACCUUCCUGUUCAUGCCUUUUUAAUUUCUAUUUUGGCCAGGUGCUGUGGCUUACGUUUAUAAUCCCAUCACUUUGGGAGGCCAAGGCAGGAGGAUGGCUUGAGCCUAGGAGUUCAAGACCAGUCUGGACAACUUGGUAAAAUCCUAUCUCUACUAAAAAUACCAAAAUUAGCCAGGCAUGGUGGCAUGUACCUGUAACCCUAGCUACUCAGGAGGCUGAGGCAUGAGAAUCACUUGAAUCUGGGAGGUGGAGGUGCAGUGAGCUGAGAUCACGCCACAGCACUCCAGCCUGGGUGACAGAGCAAGACUGUCUCAAAAAAAAAAAAAAAAGAAAAGAAAAGAAAAAGUGAAAAGCAUGCAAAUUUAUAUCAUAUAAAUUUACGUGACUAAGACCUGGAGAAACAGAUAAUGUGUAUUUAUGUUUAGGUUUGAUGAAGAGUGGACAAUCGUGGAGAAAUACGAUUGGACAAAAGGGAUGAAACAGAAAGGCUAAAGAGGGCUGGAGUCAGGGGACUUCUCUUCCACCAGAUGGAGUCUCACUCUCUCCCCCAGGCUGGGGUGCAGCGGCGUGAUCUCAGCUCACUCCAACCUCUGCUUCCCAGGUUCAAGCGAUUCUUCUGCCUCAGCCUCCGGAUACCUGGGAUUACAGCUUCACGGUGAUGAUAUGGCAUCUGCCAGCUCUAGCCGGGCAGGAGUGGCCCUGCCUUUUGAGAAGUCUCAGCUCACUUUGAAAGUGGUGUCCGCAAAGCCCAAGGUGCAUAAUCGUCAACCUCGAAUUAACUCCUACGUGGAGGUGGCGGUGGAUGGACUCCCCAGUGAGACCAAGAAGACUGGGAAGCGCAUUGGGAGCUCUGAGCUUCUCUGGAAUGAGAUCAUCAUUUUGAAUGUCACGGCACAGAGUCAUUUAGAUUUAAAGGUCUGGAGCUGCCAUACCUUGAGAAAUGAACUGCUAGGCACCGCAUCUGUCAACCUCUCCAACGUCUUGAAGAACAAUGGGGGCAAAAUGGAGAACAUGCAGCUGACCCUGAACCUGCAGACGGAGAACAAAGGCAGCGUUGUCUCAGGCGGAGAGCUGACAAUUUUCCUGGACGGGCCAACUGUUGAUCUGGGAAAUGUGCCUAAUGGCAGUGCCCUGACAGAUGGAUCACAGCUGCCUUCGAGAGACUCCAGUGGAACAGCAGUAGCUCCAGAGAACCGGCACCAGCCCCCCAGCACAAACUGCUUUGGUGGAAGAUCCCGGACGCACAGACAUUCGGGUGCUUCAGCCAGAACAACCCCAGCAACCGGCGAGCAAAGCCCCGGUGCUCGGAGCCGGCACCGCCAGCCCGUCAAGAACUCAGGCCACAGUGGCUUGGCCAAUGGCACAGUGAAUGAUGAACCCACAACAGCCACUGAUCCCGAAGAACCUUCCGUUGUUGGUGUGACGUCCCCACCUGCUGCACCCUUGAGUGUGACCCCGAAUCCCAACACGACUUCUCUCCCUGCCCCAGCCACACCGGCUGAAGGAGAGGAACCCAGCACUUCGGGUACACAGCAGCUCCCAGCGGCUGCCCAGGCCCCCGACGCUCUGCCUGCUGGAUGGGAACAGCGAGAGCUGCCCAACGGACGUGUCUAUUAUGUUGACCACAAUACCAAGACCACCACCUGGGAGCGGCCCCUUCCUCCAGGCUGGGAAAAACGCACAGAUCCCCGAGGCAGGUUUUACUAUGUGGAUCACAAUACUCGGACCACCACCUGGCAGCGUCCGACCGCGGAGUACGUGCGCAACUAUGAGCAGUGGCAGUCGCAGCGGAAUCAGCUCCAGGGGGCCAUGCAGCACUUCAGCCAAAGAUUCCUCUACCAGUCUUCGAGUGCUUCGACUGACCAUGAUCCCCUGGGCCCCCUCCCUCCUGGCUGGGAGAAGAGACAGGACAAUGGACGGGUGUAUUACGUGAACCAUAACACUCGCACGACCCAGUGGGAGGAUCCCCGGACCCAGGGGAUGAUCCAGGAACCAGCUCUGCCCCCAGGAUGGGAGAUGAAAUACACCAGCGAGGGGGUGCGAUACUUUGUGGACCACAAUACCCGCACCACCACCUUUAAGGAUCCUCGCCCGGGGUUUGAGUCGGGGACGAAGCAAGGUUCCCCUGGUGCUUAUGACCGCAGUUUUCGGUGGAAGUAUCACCAGUUCCGUUUCCUCUGCCAUUCAAAUGCCCUACCUAGCCACGUGAAGAUCAGCGUUUCCAGGCAGACGCUUUUCGAAGAUUCCUUCCAACAGAUCAUGAACAUGAAACCCUAUGACCUGCGCCGCCGGCUCUACAUCAUCAUGCGUGGCGAGGAGGGCCUGGACUAUGGGGGCAUCGCCAGAGAGUGGUUUUUCCUCCUGUCUCAUGAGGUGCUCAACCCUAUGUAUUGUUUAUUUGAAUAUGCCGGAAAGAACAAUUACUGCCUGCAGAUCAACCCCGCCUCCUCCAUCAACCCGGACCACCUCACCUACUUUCGCUUUAUAGGCAGAUUCAUCGCCAUGGCGCUGUACCAUGGAAAGUUCAUCGACACGGGCUUCACCCUCCCUUUCUACAAGCGGAUGCUCAAUAAGAGACCAACCCUGAAAGACCUGGAGUCCAUUGACCCUGAGUUCUACAACUCCAUUGUCUGGAUCAAAGAGAACAACCUGGAAGAAUGUGGCCUGGAGCUGUACUUCAUCCAGGACAUGGAGAUACUGGGCAAGGUGACGACCCACGAGCUGAAGGAGGGCGGCGAGAGCAUCCGGGUCACAGAGGAGAACAAGGAAGAGUACAUCAUGCUGCUGACUGACUGGCGUUUCACCCGAGGCGUGGAAGAGCAGACCAAAGCCUUCCUGGAUGGCUUCAACGAGGUGGCCCCGCUGGAGUGGCUGCGCUACUUUGACGAGAAAGAGCUGGAGCUGAUGCUGUGCGGCAUGCAGGAGAUAGACAUGAGCGACUGGCAGAAGAGCACCAUCUACCGGCACUACACCAAGAACAGCAAGCAGAUCCAGUGGUUCUGGCAGGUGGUGAAGGAGAUGGACAACGAGAAGAGGAUCCGGCUGCUGCAGUUUGUCACCGGUACCUGCCGCCUGCCCGUCGGGGGAUUUGCCGAACUCAUCGGUAGCAACGGACCACAGAAGUUUUGCAUUGACAAAGUUGGCAAGGAAACCUGGCUGCCCAGAAGCCACACCUGCUUCAACCGUCUGGAUCUUCCACCCUACAAGAGCUACGAACAGCUGAGAGAGAAGCUGCUGUAUGCCAUUGAGGAGACCGAGGGCUUUGGACAGGAGUAACCGAGGCCGCCCCUCCCACGCCCCCCAGCGCACAUGUAGUCCUGAGUCCUCCCUGCCUGAGAGGCCACUGGCCCCGCAGCCCUUGGGAGGCCCCCGUGGAUGUGGCCCUGUGUGGGACCACACUGUCAUCUCGCUGCUGGCAGAAAAGCCUGAUCCCAGGAGGCCCUGCAGUUCCCCCGACCCGCGGAUGGCAGUCUGGAAUAAAGCCCCCUAGUUGCCUUUGGCCCCACCUUUGCAAAGUUCCAGAGGGCUGACCCUCUCUGCAAAACUCUCCCCUGUCCUCUAGACCCCACCCUGGGUGUAUGUGAGUGUGCAAGGGAAGGUGUUGCAUCCCCAGGGGCUGCCGCAGAGGCCGGAGACCUCCUGGACUAGUUCGGCGAGGAGACUGGCCACUGGGGGUGGCUGUUCGGGACUGAGAGCGCCAAGGGUCUUUGCCAGCAAAGGAGGUUCUGCCUGUAAUUGAGCCUCUCUGAUGAUGGAGAUGAAGUGAAGGUCUGAGGGAGCGGGCCCUGGGGCGAGGCCAUCUCUGCCUGCCUCCCUAGCAGGCGCCAGCGGUGGAGGCUGAGUCGCAGGACACAUGCCGGCCAGUUAAUUCAUUCUCAGCCAAUGAAGGUUUGUCUAAGCUGCCUGGGUAUCCACGGGACAAAAACAGCAAACUCCCUCAGACUUUGUCCAUGUAUAAACUUGAAGUGGUUGUGUUGUAGGGUUGCAGGUUUUUUGUUACGCUGCUGUCACUUUCUGUCCAGGAGCUGGCACCCCAGGUGUUCUGAGACCUUGAGGGACCCAGACCUUUGGGUCCAAGAGUUUCCCAAACAGCCACGCCUCUCAGGAACCCACCUGGCGGUUCCGUGAGCUCAGGCAGGCCUGACCCGGCGGCACAGCCUGGCAGGGACCUCGUCCCCAAGCCUGGCAGAAUGAGAGGGGUUGAGGUCCCGAGCGCCACUCCUAGCCUUGCCGCCUUCAAUAGAGAAGAAAUCCCUUUGCUAGAUAGGGUCCCCCAGGCAGUCCCCAGUGGCGGGACACAGGGGUCCGGCUGUGGAGCUCCCCUGCCAGCCCCUGGAGCUCCAGGAGGGCCUGUUGGUCCCCUGUUCAGAAUGGAGUGCAGCCCGCCAGCGGAAAGUGUUCAUUCUGCAUAGGUGUGAGGCUUUAUCUGCACACAGGACAUGAAAACCAGCAGAAAGGCCCUGAGCUGCUGCAUAGCCCCAUCUGAUUUCUGCAGUUCCCGCCAGCCUCCAACACGGGGACUCUGCCGUAACUGGAAUCUUCAUAGGUCAUAUUGAAAUCUUCAAGGUGACCAUGCCCCACCGGGGUGCUGGGGCAGUAGUCAUGGCAGACUCCCGGCCUGGGCCCCCAGGAUUCUAGGACCCCCAGGCAGCCCCUUGGACUGGUCCCGGGUGCCUUCCAAGCACAGUCUCCAUGCUCCCAGAUUCUCGACCUUCCCCCGGCCCGGGAGGUGCAGCCUGCGUCUGCCUCUGUCGUGUGUGCUGAUUUGAGUGGCUUAGCUUGCCACAGCGCAGCCUCUUCUGUCCCUUUCAGUCAUUUGCUGUACUUCCCUGUGGCACGUUACCAUGGAAGCCGCUCCAGGGUGGGUCAGGGUGCAAGCUGCUGGUGAGGUUUGGAAGCAUCAGGCUCACGGGUGUUCAUGUGUGUUCGUGCGUGUGUGUGCGUACGUGUAUAUAACUGAAGUGUCUGUACGGAAUGCCCUUUGCUAGCCAUGGGCUGGUCACCAGAUUGUUUUGUAAUGCCCGCCCCUUGCCUCGAUAUUGCCAGUUUCUUGUGCAAUAAACAAUCAGCAGCUG